AUUCAGCAGAGAACAGUAAUGCCUAGCUUCCGUUUUUAACUUAACACUUCAGUAGAACAUUUUCUUCCAAGAGGGAGAUUUUGGCCUAAGUAAAGUAGUGGGCUCUUUUUUAAAAAAAAAUUAAUUUUACUUUAAUGUGAGCAAAUCUGUAUUGGUAUGGUGUUCUGCAAUGCAUUACACUGACUUUGAAAAUUUCGAGUACUAAUGCCUUAUGUCUGGGGUUACCAUUCCCUGUGCAUCACAUACUAGUUAGUUAACAUAGCAUUUUGCUUUUCCCAUGUAAUUUUUUCCCUAUAUAAUACUGGAUUCCUGAUACUAAUUGACUUGAUACAAAAGAAUGGCUGGAUGAUAUCCAGAUAACGUAUAAUACAUGGGCUUCACCACAAUCAGGCUCUGAAUAAAUACAGACCUGUCAGAGAUUGAUAAAAUAAACUACAAUGGAUAGUGCUGUUUAAACAGUCCAUUCAAUAACAUAUAUAAGCCAGCCUGCCUUCCAUUGUGUCUGAAAUUCUUAUUUUUGUAGGUAAACAAAUGCACAUUCAGCACUGAUUGAAUAGCCCCUUGAACUAUGCUCCACAGUUUGCGUUUGGGUUAAUCUUGUCGGUUUUAAUAUAGAGAGAAAAAAGCUCAAAGCACCAGGGGUGGAAUUGUUAGUGCUUUCACAUCCACAUUCCUCACAUUUUGUCAGGAUGAUAAACUGUAGGUAAUGGACUGUCGUUGUUCUGCAGGACAACUGAGCCAGGCAGAGCACAAAGACUAAGCUAAAGCGAUACCUCACAACAUGCUUGGUAGCCUUCUUUUCAGAUGAGAAUUUAUUUGAGAAUCAUGUGUCUAGGGACUGCACAUCUUAACCUCAACAGUUACAGCUUCAAGCCCCAGAAACAGGAGCUGGAGGUUAAGAUGAUUUGCUAAGCACCUGGUUCUAAAUCUUUUACAAAGCAUAAGCUGUUGACGCUGGUUCUGCCGACGCAAAGACAUGCAGAUGACUCCAACAUUUCCAGAGGCUUCUGACUUAAGCUAAAGUGUGUGGACAGGUGAAUUCGCCAUGGGCCUGGAGACCAGCUUGCUAAAAACUAUGUGUUUGAAUGGUUCCUCCAGACAGAGUCAGCUGAAGAACAAUUGGUGGAUUUAUAUUAAAACCUCUUGUCUGUAAACUUACUGAGGUGCAUCCUUCGGUUGGUGGAUCAGUGAGAUAAUUGCCUUCAGAUGGACAUUGCAACUGGAGCAACUAAAUCCUUGCUGUCUUUCCUUCCUCUGAAAUCUUCCAGGUAGCUCCCGAGAGCUUCAGUAUGACACCAAACUUCGGGCGACGUUUUAGAGUGCGUUCACCUAAUGGGAAACUAUUCGAGAUCCCAGCGUGACUGCAGUAAUGCGUCAUAGGAAUGGGAGUGGCAGGGGAAAAGGAAAUACAGAUUGUAGACCCUAAUAAAAAAAUUUUUAGGAAAGAUAUUUCUUUAACGUUUUAUGAGAACUUCAUUCUUAAAAUACUUAAUUGCAAAUUAGACAAAUAGAAGUGCUCUUCUAAGGAAGGUGAUUAAACUGGUCCUCCUAUCAGCCUAAUCUCUGCCUGCCUUUGCUGCUGACAUAAAGAACCUGUUUUUCAGGUCACUUAAUAUACAUCUACAUAGAUUUGCUUAUGAGCUCACCCUUUGUGUAGCGGAGUAGAGCCUUAAAGAGGAGUGCUCAACUGUUUAAAAUAUUUUGAUUAAAAUAUGCAGAACCCAUAGAACUAUAAGCUUCUAGUCAGGAAUUAGCUCUUUCAGGGAACAGCUCCCCCCUUCUUUUUAAGGGGGGAAUUAGAAGGAGGCUGGGGGAGGAAUAUAAGAACAGCAAAGAAGGAAGGAUAGCAAAUGGGACAUGUUCCGAACAGCUUGGAAAAACUCCUGUGGCUUCAUUGUCUCUAUAAAGCCAAAGAAUACAAAGACAUAAGCAAUUCAGCCCUUCUCCCAUGAUGGAAGAUGUAAACCGUUGACAUGCCUCCCCUGUUUAACUUGUUUAAUUCUCAUUUUAAAUUCAGCACGAUACUAGCCGUGUGAACUCUGAAGAUUUCUUUAGUAAUCCAUUUUGUAGUUCCGAAUCAAAAACAAAGUGAAAGGGUCUGACACAAUUUGCUUUUAUUUUUAGGCAAAUCAACCCUGGUCAUAGUUAAUAAGGGGAUUACAACUCAGACUAGGUCUUUACAGAUGUGAUGUAAAUCAAGGGCAGAGUAUAAAGAAACUGAUCCCUUUUGAUUGAAGUAUAGUAAAAAGGCAUAGAGAAACUAGCAGCAGUAAUCUGAUUGUAUGGCAAUAAAACCACCAUUUUCUGUCUUUCAGAUAAAAAUAAUGUGGUAAAUCCAUGCAGUUCAUAAGAUGUAAAGGCAGAUAAAGGGUGAAGCCAUGGCAACAUAUAGAUUAGCUUGAUGUUAGAAAUGACACGUCUCUGAAAAGGGCGCGGGACGAAGGCCCUUGCCUCCAGGCUGUUGGGCAUUAUGUGAGAACCACACAGACUUGGAAACUGGGAUUAGGAAGUAUGAAAGCUCUACUUGUGGUCUGGGAUGGCUGAGGCAGUAAAGAAAAGCUGCUCAGUUCUUGCUCAUUGGUGGUGGAUAAUAUGGCAAAGGUAGAUUUCAUUGACUGCCUUUUUUAUAGAUUGAGAUUGGGGCUGAUUAAAACUUCAGAUCACUGCAGUUGUUAGGGCCUGGGAGAUUUUCCUUUUUAACUCCUGGCCUAACAGCAGCAGCCGUUCUGUAGGAUUAACUGCACUUCGCGGUCGUUGCCUUAAUCUAUUUGGGCUUCAGGCAGGGACAUGCUGGGAAGGAACAGAGACCAGAGGGGAUAGGUAGGGCUGGGGUUAUCUGAAAAGAAAACAGAGACCUUUUGAUUUCAGCCAUCUUUUCAGACCCAGCUCCCUCUCCCGCUGCAUGGGAGAAGCAAAGGUAAACAGGACACAUUGUCCCUCUCCCUCAGCCACAGAGCUCUUCUGUGAGUUUUGUCUUUCCCACCCUGGAAAAAAAGAUAAAAUACAAUUUUUAAAAGGGGAGGGAGGAAUUUAGUUUUAAUUCAAAUGAGUAGUAAUCCAAUAUGCCAAAAGCAGUGGGCUCUACCUAGAUGUAAUUUUACUCGUAAAUGUGAGUCUUAAACUUUGAGUUGAAUGGGGCAGGCUGUUAGAGGUGGUGUAAAUUACAGGAUUAUAAAAAUGUUAGUGCUGCCCAGCCUUAAAGUCAAAAACAGAAAAAUCUCUGUGCUGUUGAGUCUUCCCGCCCUCUCUCCUGAACAACCUUGUAAGUAAGCUAGACUUUUGUUUUUGCCUUCCAUACUUUCCAUUUCAGCCAUUAAACAAAAUAAGCCAUUGAAACCACGAUUGGGUUCCAUGCAGAGUGACAUCCGCAAUCGGGUCAAGCCAGAAGGAAAUACUUGCUCGAUUGCCCCCUAUUUGGCAUUACAGGAAAGUCUCCACACUUUGGAAGAGUCUGAACUCUCAAGACAUUGAAAAUGCCAAAGGCUGCAAACACCCUGUGUCUUUCUUGAUGGAGUGCAUCUUGGUGUGUUUUACAAAGGGGAAUUCAGUGCUGUUUUUUUGUUGUUGUUGUUGUUUUUUUUUUUUAAAGAGCAGCAUAGGGCCCUUCUAGACUCUUGGAUUCUGUGUCUGACAAAAAUGGUCAUUAAAUGAGCAAUAUUAUAAUUUAGACCCAUUUCACUGAUUUUGUUCCAAAUUCUCAACUGACUUGAGCAUCUGUUUGGGGCUGUAGAUACAUUGCCCUUGUUGACUGUUUUUCUCGUUUCUAUGGGAAUUACUGUAGCCAUUACUAUGUAGCUUUCAUAGACUCAAAACAUUUUUAAAGUAUUGCAUAUAGGCUGGCCAUAUCCAGUGCCUGUUACUUUACCUUCUUUUUCUAACUUAAUGCAGCAGUCUGUAUUAACAGAUCCAUUUCAUUUGUCUAGCUUCAUCAGAGAGAGGCUACCCCCUGAUUUACAGGCUGCUCACAUCCAAGCACCUUGCAUUCUACACUUGACAGUGAUUGCUAAUGGCCCAUUCAACUAAAGUAUUUGCUUGUUAACAGGGAACAGAACAUGAUAAAUGUCCAGCAAGCUUGCUGCCUCCUUCAGCUUUUCAAACGCAGACUGGUGCAUAUUUAUGGCAGGCAAAUGACAAAAGAAAAAGCUGAAUUGCCCUGGCCUCCAGCUUUCUAUCAGAAACAGGGUUAAAGUGAUUAAAGCAAUCAUUCAAGAAAGCCCUGCCGUUUGUUUACUAACCUUCAUCCAACAUUUAGCUUUGUAGUCUACCUGUGAGAAGAUAUUUCAGAAGUAUUAGAGAUAAGGAAGGAGGAUCUAGCAAACCAGUGAAAAGAGUAGGUGACCAGUUAUAAAAUGCUUUCCAUGCACAUUGAAUGCCAGGCGAACCUAUUUCUGUUAUUCCAGCAGACAAUCAGCAGUGGCUCUAGAUUAUUAACAUAUUUUCCUUUCAUGUAUAAAUUCAAAUAUGUAAUUCUAGUCCAAAGCAUUCUGUGGCUGGUAAGCACAUACUUGCUGAUUUCAAAUAAGAAAACAUAGCAAGGGAAAGCUCCAUUAAACAAGUUGUUUCUGCCCUUAGUAAUUCUCUAAACAAGAUAGGAAGAAAAAGUGGACAGUAGUGGAGUAUUAAUAGUGUGCUCUUUUCAUUCUCUAAAGCACGAGUAAGUAAGCGUUCAAACUACUCUGUGGUGGGCAUACAUUUAGAGCGCUGUGAAUGAACCACUGCUGUUCUGCCAUACUUAAUUUAUUUAUAUUAUUAUUUUUAUUUUAUUGUUGUUUUUAUGUAUUAUUAUAAUUAUUUAUUUAUAUUACUAAUUUAUUUUCUCAAUUUAAAUCCUGUUGCAUCCAAUUUUAAUUACAGUUUUUGUAUCUGCCUUCCCAUACUUGCUACCCACGUCCCCAUUGCCACUGCGGCCUUAUCCAUGUUUUCUGUGUACACCACUCUCGUAUCACCCCAGAAUAAUUAUGAGUGCUACCCAGACUUUUGAAACCACUAGAGUCAACAUGUUUGUCUUUGAGGAAAGCCAAUGAUGCUUUAGCAUUUUUGGCAGGGGUGGAUGUGUGUUUAAGUGGGGUGGGUGCAGCUCCUUAUUGUCUGCCUAUUCUACUGUUGUUCCCAAUCCACAUUCCCUGCGGGGCACCUAACCUGUGUGCAUAGCAAAGAAUUUCCGACCUUCAGAGCCAGAAGUGUUUCUCAAUUGAUCUCUUCCAGCCUAGGGUUAUAGCUGAUGAAUUAUAAUCCUUGCUCUUUCCACACCUUUACCUGGGCUUACCAUGGCCCUAAAACAUUUGCCCAGAAUCAGAAUUGUCUCAUGAGUGAGUGGGGCAAGGCAAAUCCUGUUCCAGACCAGCUGAGAAUGUACCUAGCUGCAGAAGAAGUUAGAAAGUGUCAUCUUUUACUUAUCUACCAGAACUAUAUUCGAGGUACAUUUUAGAUUUAAAAAAAAAGCAAGUUCUCGUAGGCCUUGAAUCCCCCCCUUGCUAUGGGAAAAUGGAUCAUUAUUAUAAUGGACUGUCCAGUAAAGUUCAUGAUUUCUCCUAGACAUGUUCUCUCUCUUUAUGACCUAGAUCAAGAGUGAUCUCUUUAAGUCUUUUCUUCAUAAUCCCACAGCACUUUGUACUUAGAUGUACUUAGAAAGAACCAUAUACACGGUACGUCAUGAUUGAUAUGCAAGCCUUCACCACUCUACCUGUCCUAAAAGUCAGGGACACACCUUCUUCAUUUCAUCAGUCCCUACUUCUAUCCAGCAUUGGCAUCCAGUAAGUAUUAGUGGAAUGGACAGACAACCCGAAUUUGUGCUGAUGGCAGUUUACCCUGUUUUAACUGUCAUCCUUCUGCUACUAGACAUGGAUGAGACCUGAGACGAUGGGACUGCUCAGAGGUCCCUGGCUCUUGAACUUUAGGGCACCAGAAUCCCCUGCAGGGCUUGAGAAAACAGGGGUUUCUGGGCCCCACCCCCAGAGUUCCUGAUUCCUGAGGUCUGGGGUGGGGCUUGAAGAUGGACAUGUUUAACAAGCUCCCAGGUGACGCUGGCAACUGCUGCCUCAGGGCCAUGCUGAGAACCCUCGCCCUACACAAACCUUUCUGGGAAAACAACUCAACAUUAAAGCUGUUUGGGGAUCUCUGAAGAAAUCUGUAGUCCUUGCCUUGUUGGGGGAGCAUCAGGGAUCUAACCAUUGAUGGUGGAGUAUUUGUUGUUAAUUCAGCAAGCAACUAUUAAGUGUUAGGCCUGUUACUCGGCUCUAACAAUACAAGGCAGAGUGACCUGUACCCUCGAGAUUUAAAGUCUAAGUCCUGUAGAGAGAAGCCCAGGUGGGAGCAAGCACAUUUAGAGUUAGGUGCUUGGUGCAAGGUGGGGACACAGAAGAAGGGAAUGGCAUUUGCCUCUGGAGGGGUCCGGAAACAGCCUAGGGAGGAGGAGCUUGAGUCUUGAAAUACUGUGGGCAUCUCUAAGCAAAGUCACAGUAGACAGCUGAAAUAAAGAAAAUAGUAAGCAAGCCAAAGAAACAGUAUUUCAGCCAAGGGCAGCGUGUGUCUAUCACGUCCACCUGUGAACACGUCCCAGGAUUCUCUGCAUCCGGCCAUUGCUCAAGACAGAUCCCUCACAGGAACAGCUAAGCCACUGAUUUCAGCUACCUGUUCACGUGAGAAUUAUCAGUACCUACUGCUUUUCAAAAUGAGUAUGAUCAUGGAUAGGUGAGGCAAUUCAGUUUCGCAGAGACAGUAGGGCAAGUGCCACUGUAGUUUAGUUAAGGGCACAUGCUUUAGAGUUUGGCUAUGUGAGUCCAAUCCCAGUUUAGCCAUUUAUUAGCUGGGUAGCUUUAGGAGCAGUAGCCUUAGUGUCUCUCAGUUGUCCCAUCUCUAUAAUAGGGACAAUAACAUAAUAGUGCUGAAUAAAAGAGUAACAAAAUUUUGGUCAACAUUUAAUGUAUUUAAAGAGCUAAGCUCCGUGAUUGGCACAAUGAACCAAUCAAUCAAACACCAGUUGUUAUUAAUAAAAGUCAGUUGAAUAUGUACUGUGUGCCUGGCCGUGGUUCAAUUUGCCUUUGCAUACAAGGAAAAAAUUAAAAUACUCUGUUAAUAAAGACUAUAGCAUAAUACUUUCACCUUAAACUUCUUGAUGUUAAUUUAUUUUGUUUACCUGCCAAACUUCUACUCAUUCCUUAUGACUUUCUGCUACAUGAAACACCCUUUGUAAUUCUUUUGUCCUAUUAAAUUAAGUUCUCUCUCCUCUGCUUUCCUGCUUUUGGUGCUUUCUAAUAACACUUUUAACCCUGGACUUUCUCAUUCAGCUGUGCAACUGUGGACUGAGAGGAGGCUCUUUGAAUUCAUUUUGUAUAUUCUAGUAGAGAGUACUGUGAGCAGUUGGGUUGUUGAAUGAAUACAUUAAUUCAACCUGGAGGGAUGGGCAGUAUUGCAUUUUUUACAUUGAUAUUACAUGAUAUUUAGAAAACUGCUUAACUGGUGGACGUUGUUUUAUUAACAGCAUUUUGUGUAUAGCACUCACUAUGUGCCAGCUGCUAUUCUAACUGCCUGACAAAUACUCCUGAAACCUUCAUGGUAACCAUAUGAGGGAAGCACUUUUAAUAUAUCCAUAAUACCAACGGGGAGACUGUGGCCAAAUUGGUUAAUUAACUUAGCCAAAGUCAUAUUGAACUAAUAAGUGGAUUUAAACCCAGCUAGUCUGGGGCCAGGGUCCCUCUUUUAAUCUUCUGCCUCCUGCUUAUGCUGUUGCAUGGAGUAGUCUUUAUCAUAUAACUAAAUUAAGCAUGCAUUUGCUUAAAGCAGUGCAUACAUGAUGGAUCAAAAAGUUUGUGGUAUAAUUGGUUUAAUUCUGUCAUUAUCCAUUUUGAUUUAUAGUCACUUUCUUAUGAUGGUCGUGUAGUUUUAAAUGGAACCUUUGAAUCUUUGAUAUAAUAAGGUUAUGUCAAAUCUUGGGUAUAAUAAGGUUAUACCCAAUGGAAACAGAAUAAUGAUCAGCCCAUUUAAAGGAUGACUGGAGAGUUAUUACAAUACAUAAUAGUCAUGCAUAUAUUGAGUAGUAUUCCUUUGGUAACAUUUUCCUUUUAAAAAUUGUAACAUUUGAUUGUUCCUUGUUGGGAGAAAAGGAGGUCAGAUUUUUGAGGGGAGAUCCAUUUGGUGAGAUGCUGAGUGUGUGUCAAGCUAAGGAGAUAGUAUGACAUCUUUUUUAGAGUCUAGUCACAAUUAAAUGCCAUUUUAUUUUGGAUUUUGGGAUCCGUGCCAGCUUCCAGCUUGUCAGAGCUGAGAAGACUCAAAUCAAGUCCAGGCUUAUUUCUACAGCAAACUGGGAUUCUGGCUUCUUGCCGGUGGAUUCAUUCAGUACAGCCCAUCUGGCUUUUGAUGUUCUGCAAGUUUGGAGCCAUUUGUUGAAGGAAGCCAGGCGGUGAAUAUUGGUGGUCCUGGGGUUCUCUUGACUCCAAGUGGUGCCCCUUGGUUUGCAUUUUCACCAUGCUUAGCAUCUGCUUACCUGGAGACCAUGCAGCCGCCGGCCAGAGGUCUCCAACAACCAAAUCUUCAUGCCUUUUAGAACUCAGAGUCCCCAGCACAUCCUCCUUCCUCCUCCUUGUCCAAUUACUUUCAUGCAGUUCUCAGUAGCUGCUUGUUUGAAUCACUUAUAGUAUUUAACUUCUAGGGUGUUUUUGGGUUUUGGUCAAGGUAAUUCCAGGCUGAAUGUGGUGACUAAGCAGGAAAUAAAUGGGUCGUCCUCAAAGUUACAGUGGAGCGCUGUUUCUAUUUUCCUAAGGUACACAGUUGUGGGGGCGAUCCGUAUGGAAGUCAGGAACCCAGUCUGAUUUUGCUUCCUUUUGAUGGUAGCAGUACAGACCUGGCUGUUUUGUAGCCUGCUUUGUUUUUCUUCCUUUUCUUCCCUAACUUCACGGGCUGUGGCAAAGCCCUGAGACGUGCAGGAAAAUGUCUCCUGUCAUACGCCCACAGCAGACCUAGCCCUGACCCUCCUCUGAAGCCCAGGAAGGAGGUAUCUGUGAAGCAGCCUGCUUGUAAAGCAAUUGCACACAGCCUUGUAAACUGUGUUACUGGGCUGAUUAUACUUGAUUGGCAAGGUGAAUCUCUUAUAGCAAAAGAGAACUUGGAGAGUUUUAUCUCAUCUUAUGCCUUAUUAAUUUGUUCAUUCUUUAAUUACACAGCCACCUAUUGAGCACCCUAUUUAUGCAAGGUACCUGGUCGGGGGUCAGAGGGAGGGUCCCAUGGUAAACGAGACAGACUCAAUCCUGGAGGAGCAGGAAUGGCAGCCCCUCGCUGGGCUGUUGGCCCCACCAAAAGGGAAAGGUUUCAUUUUAAUAAUACAUGGGUGAAUCAUUUUUGUCAAUAGGCAAAAUUCUUUGUAGUUAAAAAAAAAUAUGAUGGUAGGAAGGAAAGGGAUGGGCAGAGGGUUAAAACAAAAGAUAUGCUCUCCCUAACUCUAGAUUGUAGUAUUGUUAUGCUUGUCACUGUAGCUGAAUUCCAUUUCUUUGAGUUUUUUCAAUGCCAAGGCAUUCCCUGUAUGACUUACGUGAGCCUUUCAUCUCCGCGAUUUUUCCCAUUCAGGUAAAUGAGCAAAUGGAUUUGAACACUCAUAUCUAAAACAAGAGAGAACCAGCUGGAAAUGCCCUUUGAAUUUCUUUCUCUAUGUAAACCAUUUUUCUUUCUGGUGCCUCACCUAUAAAUAACAGGAGUUCCACCUUCCUUUAUAGACUCUUGCUGAAAGCAUGGUUUGGAACAAGACCGUACAGGUGCACACAAAUUACAGUUGGGAAAGAAGCCUGCAGUGCAUCUUGUCUCUGAAGGUUAUGAAAUCCUCCUUUUAGUAAUGGAGCUGGCGUGAUCAAGCCAGCAGGAUGAAAUUUGGCAUUUGUGAGAUCACCCCCCUUCUCACUUGCCCACUGUACAUAGCAUCCCAGCCUUACUCUUCAAAUCUCCACAUUUUUUCUUAUCUAGCUACAAAAUUCAUAGGCUGAUUUUUUUGGGGUGCGUGUGUGGUUUUUUUUUUGUUUUUUUGGUAAAUAAAGACCUGCAUUUUUAUUUUGAUAUAGGUGGUUGAGUUUUGUCUUUAAUUUCAUGACAGAGAUUUAACUAGUCUCAACUUUUGAAAAGACAACAAUGAUAUUUGGGGAUCACACACUUAAAGUUAGAUUUCUAGAUGAUUAAUACCAAAGUAGAUGAUUUUUUAGCCUCAGCCAUUUAUAGGUAUGCCCUUCUGUGAAUUUUUUAUGACAGUGAAAAUCAUGGCACAGAUAAAAAUUAAAUAAAUACUUCUGUUAUUUUCCUGAAGAAAAAAAAAAAAAGCUUAAACUAUGAGAAUACUGUCUUUGAGCACUUUAAAAUAAAAUUGACUUCAGCCAGCAGGAUUUUGAGCAUUACAUCACAAAUAAAAAACAAGAUUAACAUCAAAAGGAGUCAGUUUUCAUUCAAUUGUGCAGCACUGUGGGCUGUGAAAUUUAAUAUUAUUUUGACUCAUAUGCUAAUUGUAGACUGACAGAGGAAAAUGGAUUGUGUUUAAAUAAAAGGAUACACAGCAUCACACGCAGCUGUAUCAAAUACAAGUUGAGGUCUUUGGGCCAGGAACUGGGGGCCCUCUAGCUCUGUUAUUGCAGAUUCAAGUUUGACAAAUAAAACUUUCCUUUAGACUGUAGUUUAAUUACUUUUUUUCAAAGGUAUGCGUGAUGAAGAGGCACAAAUACACCUCACCUUGAAGAGUUGCUAAACUGGUUUGUGUGCCGAUCAGUUCACCGUGUGUUUGAAUUUCUGUGCUUCUCAUCUUUCCUUUUCUUGAAAAGAUUUUGCUUGUCAUUGGUGUGAAUUGUACCCCCCACCCCCACCCAUCUAGUCUUUGCUCUCAGAUUUAUAACACUUUAAUGGUUCCAAAUUGUAUAGCCUGCUCUUAGACCCCUUUUCUUUUCCUUGAAUAAAUCAGGUUCAUGUUGCAGACGAUAUUUGUUUUAGGAAAGUGUGAAAGAAGGGGCACCUGUGAAAACACGCAAUUGUUCCAACACACAUAUACAUCCAAAUUAAAGCAGAAAAUGUCAAAGCCUCCAAUCACUACCUUAUUUCUUGGAGGUUUAAAGCCGCUGAGAAGAUAGUGGUGCCCUCGCUGGAAGUUUUAAGGUAAUUACUUUUUACUCUAAGCAGUAGUAUCUGGUAACCUAAUUCCGUAUAAACCUGACACCCUAUCGCUACACCCCAGUAUUUCUCUGAUUUCAGAAUAAGUCUGCGUAGAAACUUGUUCUGAUGUUAAAGUGCAAAAGGGGGCAGUAAAGUGCUAUCCACAAAAAAGGAAAAACAUUUUCCAAGUAUUUCUUAUUACUGCCUGUGUCUUUCGUAGGCCCUGCCUUUAUUUAUUCAUUUUAUAACAAAACUCUUAUGUUUGGGGCAUUCAGAGAAUACCUUAUUAAGCUGUUGCAGCAAUCUAGCAUUAAAUGGAAGACAUGCAAGACUGAAGAUCCUGCCUGUUUAUGAAGUGUGCCAUCAAAUUCACAUGCUCAUGAUGCAGAGUCCUUCUUUGGGAGUAUUCGUAUUCCCAAGUGCACAGAGCACUUCGGAAAGGAGCCUUGGUCUUUGGUGUUAAUGCUCUCCUAGCUCCGUAUAGAUGUGGCAGGCCCAAAGUACAUGGUGGGGUGAAGGGUCAAGGGUUUGGGCUUAUCCAGAGCAGCGUGCAUCCUUUGUCAGGAGGUGACUGGAAACACCAGCCAAUUACAGCAGAACUGCAGACUGCUCAUCUGCAUUCGGAAUUGCAGAUGAACCAGUUUGUACUCGACUUCUCUUCUUCACUGUAGGCUUUGACAUUUAAUUAAAAAUUAAAGCCUUUUAUGGAAAAAGUACAUGUUUUCCAAAAUGGGGUAAAUUCGAAGUAUACUUGAUACAGAACACUGGCUUGGGAAUAAACCUGUGAUAUUACAUGACUUUUGGUUUGCAACUGCUAGGCUGAGCCUCUUUGUAAAGCUGGGAUUUAGAAUCUUUGAAAUGUUUGUACAGUUCAAUGAUUAAGCAUAAAUUGUAUAUAUUCCCUUUUUUUCACUUAUUUGAGUAAACAAGUUUGUUACUACAGCUUCUGUGGACUCAGAGAUUUAUGUAUUAAAUAGGCCACAACUUCAACUAGGAUAAUUUUAUUUAUCUGCUUGUUAGGGAAUUGCAUCAAAAGUUUAAGUCUGUAGGCAUUAAAUAUUUUAAAUGCUUAUUUUUAAAGUCAAUUAUGAAAGAUAGCACAAAGUUUUUCUGAAACUACAUUAAAAAAAUAAUGUUUUAAUCUUAUCACAAAAGCAUUGACUAUUUAUUGCAAAGAAAACACAGAAAGCUAAAAAUCAUUCUAAGUCCACCAUUCAGUAGCCCAAAGUGGUCUCAGGUAAAGGCGGUGUGUGUGACCAUUUGUUUAUGGUUGUCUCCGUGCAGUCAGCAAAAUAAACAGAACAACAUGCCAUAUAUUAUUGAUGUGUAUAUUUUCAACUGAAAUUAGCCAUCUGCUUACAAUGAUCAUAUACACUAAUGGUAUAAUUUUGAAAUGAAAAGAAAAAUAAAAUAAUUCUUUGUGGAGAGUAAUGCGAAUUGACUUAUGAAUCUCGCCCUGCUUGGCAGUUUGCUCUAGAGGUAGAAGAGCUUUAUGUGUGGGCCUCCUCCCCCCCCACACAUUUAUUCUGCUCACACUUGCACCAGCAUCCAUGUCAGGACUCACCUUGUCCUGUUACAUGAGUAACAUGGCCCUGAUUCUCAAGUGCAUGAUAACUGCCAUAAUUACACAUAAAUAUUAAAUAUUUAAAUAGAUCUUUACGUGUGUAAUAUUAGGUAGAAGUGGCUCUGGAUCGAAUCUGAUGCUUUUUAAAUAGAAGCUUUCCCACAACAUUUCCAAGCACUGUCAUCGUGUCUGUCUCGAUUUGGGGUUUACCUGGCCUAGUUAUCUGUCUGGGUGUAGAAACUGGUAGUUCCUGUUUGUAUCUUUUUUGUUCUGAUCUCUUUAUUCUGUGUCAGCUAAAUAUUCUUGCAGUCAGUUACUAACAUAUUAACUCAUCCUUGUUUGGAAACUUUGGCAUAUCCUUCCAUGGUUUCCUUCCGUGGACCUGUCGCGUCUCUCAGGAGAGCCACCAGGUAUAUUGUCACACAUUUCGCAUGUAUUUUCAGAGACUACAGCAGCAUCAAGUGGCCCCCCAGCGAUUUGGGUUUUCUUCUCGGUUAAUCUACACUCUUUGGCCAACCGUGAGAAAACUUGUAAGAAGGCAUCAGAUGUUUGUGCUAAGAUUUCUACCUGGACAAGGACUGGUACUAUACCCACAGAUAGGAGACAAAUUGGAUAUUAUUUGCCCCAAAGUGGACUCUAAAACUGUUGGCCAGUAUGAAUAUUAUAAAGUUUAUAUGGUUGAUAAAGACCAAGCAGACAGAUGCACUAUUAAGAAGGAAAAUACCCCUCUCCUCAACUGUGCCAAACCAGACCAAGAUAUCAAAUUCACCAUCAAGUUUCAAGAAUUCAGCCCUAACCUCUGGGGUCUAGAAUUUCAGAAGAACAAAGAUUAUUACAUUAUAUCUACAUCAAAUGGGUCUUUGGAGGGCCUGGAUAACCAGGAGGGAGGGGUGUGCCAGACAAGAGCCAUGAAGAUCCUCAUGAAAGUUGGACAAGAUGCAAGUUCUGCUGGAUCAACCAGGAAUAAAGAUCCAACAAGACGUCCAGAACUAGAAGCUGGUACAAAUGGAAGAAGUUCGACAACAAGUCCCUUUGUAAAACCAAAUCCAGGUUCUAGCACAGACGGCAACAGCGCCGGACAUUCGGGGAACAACAUCCUCGGUUCCGAAGUGGCCUUAUUUGCAGGGAUUGCUUCAGGAUGCAUCAUCUUCAUCGUCAUCAUCAUCACGCUGGUGGUCCUCUUGCUGAAGUACCGGAGGAGACACAGGAAGCACUCGCCGCAGCACACGACCACGCUGUCGCUCAGCACACUGGCCACACCCAAGCGCAGCGGCAACAACAACGGCUCAGAGCCCAGUGACAUUAUCAUCCCGCUAAGGACUGCGGACAGCGUCUUCUGCCCUCACUACGAGAAGGUCAGCGGGGACUACGGGCACCCGGUGUACAUCGUCCAGGAGAUGCCCCCGCAGAGCCCGGCGAACAUUUACUACAAGGUCUGAGAGGGACCCUGGUGGUACCUGUGCUUUCCCAGAGGACACCUAAUGUCCCGAUGCCUCCCUUGAGGGUUUGAGAGCCCGCGUGCUGGAGAAUUGACUGAAGCACAGCACCGGGGGAGAGGGACACUCCUCCUCGGAAGAGCCCGUCGCGCUGGACAGCUUACCUAGUCUUGUAGCAUUCGGCCUUGGUGAACACACACGCUCCCUGGAAGCUGGAAGACUGUGCAGAAGACGCCCAUUCGGACUGCUGUGCCGCGUCCCACGUCUCCUCCUCGAAGCCAUGUGCUGCGGUCACUCAGGCCUCUGCAGAAGCCAAGGGAAGACAGUGGUUUGUGGACGAGAGGGCUGUGAGCAUCCUGGCAGGUGCCCCAGGAUGCCACGCCUGGAAGGGCCGGCUUCUGCCUGGGGUGCAUUUCCCCCGCAGUGCAUACCGGACUUGUCACACGGACCUCGGGCUAGUUAAGGUGUGCAAAGAUCUCUAGAGUUUAGUCCUUACUGUCUCACUCGUUCUGUUACCCAGGGCUCUGCAGCACCUCACCUGAGACCUCCACUCCACAUCUGCAUCACUCAUGGAACACUCAUGUCUGGAGUCCCCUCCUCCAGCCGCUGGCAACAACAGCUUCAGUCCAUGGGUAAUCCGUUCAUAGAAAUUGUGUUUGCUAACAAGGUGCCCUUUAGCCAGAUGCUAGGCUGUCUGCGAAGAAGGCUAGGAGUUCAUAGAAGGGAGUGGGGCUGGGGAAAGGGCUGGCUGCAAUUGCAGCUCACUGCUGCUGCCUCUGAAACAGAAAGUUGGAAAGGAAAAAAGAAAAAAGCAAUUAGGUAGCACAGCACUUUGGUUUUGCUGAGAUCGAAGAGGCCAGUAGGAGACACGACAGCACACACAGUGGAUUCCAGUGCAUGGGGAGGCACUCGCUGUUAUCAAAUAGCGAUGUGCAGGAAGAAAAGCCCCUCUUCAUUCCGGGGAACAAAGACGGGUAUUGUUGGGAAAGGAACAGGCUUGGAGGGAAGGGAGAAAGUAGGCCGCUGAUGAUAUAUUCGGGCAGGACUGUUGUGGUACUGGCAAUAAGAUACACAGCUCCGAGCUGUAGGAGAGUCGGUCUGCUUUGGAUGAUUUUUUAAGCAGACUCAGCUGCUAUACUUAUCACAUUUUAUUAAACACAGGGAAAGCAUUUAGGAGAAUAGCAGAGAGCCAAAUCUGACCUAAAAGUUGAAAAGCCAAAGGUCAAACAGGCUGUAAUUCCAUCAUCAUCGUUGUUAUUAAAGAAUCCUUAUCUAUAAAAGGUAGGUCAGAUCCCCCUCCCCCCAGGUUCCUCCUUCCCCUCCCGAUUGAGCCUUACGACACUUUGGUUUAUGCGGUGCUGUCCGGGUGCCAGGGCUGCAGGGUCGGUACUGAUGGAGGCUGCAGCGCCCGGUGCUCUGUGUCAAGGUGAAGCACAUACGGCAGACCUCUUAGAGUCCUUAAGACGGAAGUAAAUUAUGAUGUCCAGGGGGAGAAGGAAGAUAGGACGUAUUUAUAAUAGGUAUAUAGAACACAAGGGAUAUAAAAUGAAAGAUUUUUACUAAUAUAUAUUUUAAGGUUGCACACAGUACACACCAGAAGAUGUGAAAUUCAUUUGUGGCAAUUAAGUGGUCCCAAUGCUCAGCGCUUAAAAAAACAAAUUGGACAGCUACUUCUGGGAAAAACAACAUCAUUCCAAAAAGAACAAUAAUGAGAGCAAAUGCAAAAAUAACCAAGUCCUCCGAAGGCAUCUCACGGAACCGUAGACUAGGAAGUACGAGCCCCACAGAGCAGGAAGCCGAUGUGACUGCAUCAUAUAUUUAACAAUGACAAGAUGUUCCGGCGUUUAUUUCUGCGUUGGGUUUUCCCUUGCCUUAUGGGCUGAAGUGUUCUCUAGAAUCCAGCAGGUCACACUGGGGGCUUCAGGUGACGAUUUAGCUGUGGCUCCCUCCUCCUGUCCUCCCCCGCACCCCCUCCCUUCUGGGAAACAAGAAGAGUAAACAGGAAACCUACUUUUUAUGUGCUAUGCAAAAUAGACAUCUUUAACAUAGUCCUGUUACUAUGGUAACACUUUGCUUUCUGAAUUGGAAGGGAAAAAAAAUGUAGCGACAGCAUUUUAAGGUUCUCAGACCUCCAGUGAGUACCUGCAAAAAUGAGUUGUCACAGAAAUUAUGAUCCUCUAUUUCCUGAACCUGGAAAUGAUGUUGGUCCAAAGUGCGUGUGUGUAUGUGUGAGUGGGUGCGUGGUAUACAUGUGUACAUAUAUGUAUAAUAUAUAUCUACAAUAUAUAUUAUAUAUAUCUAUAUCAUAUUUCUGUGGAGGGUUGCCAUGGUAACCAGCCACAGUACAUAUGUAAUUCUUUCCAUCACCCCAACCUCUCCUUUCUGUGCAUUCAUGCAAGAGUUUCUUGUAAGCCAUCAGAAGUUACUUUUAGGAUGGGGGAGAGGGGCGAGAAGGGGAAAAAUGGGAAAUAGUCUGAUUUUAAUGAAAUCAAAUGUAUGUAUCAUCAGUUGGCUACGUUUUGGUUCUAUGCUAAACUGUGAAAAAUCAGAUGAAUUGAUAAAAGAGUUCCCUGCAACCAAUUGAAAAGUGUUCUGUGCGUCUGUUUUGUGUCUGGUGCAGAAUAUGACAAUCUACCAACUGUCCCUUUGUUUGAAGUUGGUUUAGCUUUGGAAAGUUACUGUAAAUGCCUUGCUUGUAUGAUCGUCCCUGGUCACCCGACUUUGGAAUUUGCACCAUCAUGUUUCAGUGAAGAUGCUGUAAAUAGGUUCAGAUUUUACUGUCUAUGGAUUUGGGGUGUUACAGUAGCCUUAUUCACCUUUUUAAUAAAAAUACACAUGAAAACAAGAAAGAAAUGGCUUUUCUUACCCAGAUUGUGUACAUAGAGCAAUGUUGGUUUUUUAUAAAGUCUAAGCAAGAUGUUUUGUAUAAAAUCUGAAUUUUGCAAUGUAUUUAGCUACAGCUUGUUUAACGGCAGUGUCAUUCCCCUUUGCACUGUAAUGAGGAAAAAAUGGUAUAAAAGGUUGCCAAAUUGCUGCAUAUUUGUGCCGUAAUUAUGUACCAUGAAUAUUUAUUUAAAAUUUCGUUGUCCAAUUUGUAAGUAACACAGUAUUAUGCCUGAGUUAUAAAUAUUUUUUUCUUUCUUUGUUUUAUUUUAAUAGCCUGUCAUAGGUUUUAAAUCUGCUUUAGUUUCACAUUGCAGUUAGCCCCAGAAAAUGAAAUCCGUGAAGUCACAUUCCACAUCUGUUUCAAACUGAAUUUGUUCUUAAAAAAAUAAAAUAUUUUUUUCCUAUGGAAAAA